AGUUCCACGCACCCAGCGAGCCCAAGCGCCUUCUCCGCACCAGGGAAGCCCCACCCACCAGAAGCCAAGAUGUCCAGCAAGCGGGCCAAAGCCAAGACCACCAAGAAGCGGCCACAGCGGGCCACAUCCAAUGUCUUCGCAAUGUUUGACCAGUCCCAGAUCCAGGAGUUUAAGGAGGCUUUCAACAUGAUUGACCAGAACCGUGAUGGCUUCAUUGACAAGGAGGACCUGCACGACAUGCUGGCCUCGCUGGGGAAGAACCCCACAGACGAAUACCUGGAGGGCAUGAUGAGCGAGGCCCCGGGGCCCAUCAACUUCACCAUGUUCCUCACCAUGUUUGGGGAGAAGCUGAACGGCACGGACCCCGAGGAUGUGAUUCGCAACGCCUUUGCCUGCUUCGACGAGGAAGCCUCAGGUUUCAUCCAUGAGGACCACCUCCGGGAGCUGCUCACCACCAUGGGUGACCGCUUCACAGAUGAGGAAGUGGACGAGAUGUACCGGGAGGCACCCAUUGAUAAGAAAGGCAACUUCAACUACGUGGAGUUCACCCGCAUCCUCAAACAUGGCGCCAAGGAUAAAGACGACUAGGCCACCCCAGCCCCCUGACACCCCAGCCCCCGCCAGUCACCCCUCCCCGCACACACCCGUCCAUACCAGCUCCCUGCCCAUGACCCUCGCUCAGGGAUCCCCCUUUGAGGGGUUAGGGUCCCAGUUCCCAGUGGAAGAAACAGGCCAGGAGAAGUGCGUGCCGAGCUGAGGCAGAUGUUCCCACAGUGACCCCAGAGCCCUGGGCUAUAGUCUCUGACCCCUCCAAGGAAAGACCACCUUCUGGGGACAUGGGCUGGAGGGCAGGACCUAGAGGCACCAAGGGAAGGCCCCAUUCCGGGGCUGUUCCCCGAGGAGGAAGGGAAGGGGCUCUGUGUGCCCCCCAGGAGGAAGAGGCCCUGAGUCCUGGGAUCAGACACCCCUUCACGUGUAUCCCCACACAAAUGCAAGCUCACCAAGGUCCCCUCUCAGUCCCCUUCCCUACACCCUGACCGGCCACUGCCGCACACCCACCCAGAGCACGCCACCCGCCAUGGGAGUGUGCUCAGGAGUCGCGGGCAGCGUGGACAUCUGUCCCAGAGGGGGCAGAAUCUCCAAUAGAGGACUGAGCACUGCUUCUGGUCUGUGUGUCUGUGGCUGGGGUGAAGUAAGGGGACCCCGGGCCUGAAACCCUCUCCCACCUUCUCCUGCCAUCUCCAGUUACUGCCCUGCUCCUCCCACCCUGGCCCAGGGAAGGACUGGGUGUCCUCCGGCCAUAUGGUCCCUGAAGCCUCUAGGGACCAGAGUCCCUAGUAAGUGGGCUCUGUGCUCAGCUGAGACCAGCAGGGGACAGGGGACGGAGGGAAUGGGCCUCAUGGCCUUCUCAGGGCUUGUGGGAAAGGGAGGACCAUGGGAAUCACCACAGCCAAUCCCGUGGAGGGUUCCAGGCCUCUUGGGGGGCAGAGGUCAGGCCACACAGCCCUCAGGACUAAAGCUCCGGGUUCCAGAAGAACAGGGAGGCUCCAACAGUGAUGAGGCAGGCGUCCCAGCAGCUCAGGGUUGGAGGUGGGAAUGAGGGGUUUCCCAGCCCCAGGCAGGUGGAGGGCGAGUUCAGCCCCAGGACCAACAGCAUGGGGGCCACAGCUUUCCAUGUCCCUGUGUACGCAGGGCAGGCAGGGCCGGGACCCCUGCUACUGGUGGAUGAUGGGGACACUGAUGGCAGUGCCUGGGGCCUAAGAGGGGCAGAAAGAGCGCUGAAUGACUGAGCAGAGAGUCCAGAGGGGCAUGGACUGCCUGGGUCACCCAAUAGGCCUAGGGAAGAGUGAGGGCCGGACCCACCCCACCUGACCCCAGCGAGUGGACCCAGCUUGGUCCUGAGGCCUUCUCCAGAGGUCACCCAGCGCAGGCAGCCGCAGCACUCAGCAAAGGUCCCAGAUCAGGGCCAAGGGGGAGCUGAGCACCAGGGGACCCUGUGCCUGACCAGGAGGCCCUAACCUCCUGCAGGCCUCAACGCCAGGCCCUGCUCAGAGCUCGGCUGAAACUCCUCAUCCUGGCUCCAAACAGAGGCCCAAAAGUCCCUGGUAUCAACUCCAGAAGGGGCGAGACCCGAACAAGUUCCAAACCAGGCCCAAAUAGUAUCCCAAACUCAGUCCCAAACACAUUCUCACCCCCGGCAGCAGGCUGCAGGCCUCCAGCUACACACACGGCCCUGGGCAACUCUCAGUCUGGCCACCCAUUCGAUGCUGCCAGCCCCAAGGGUGUGGGAGGGGGGUCUCAGAGUGUCCCAGGGUACUGGCCACACAUGCCCGACACCAGGGUCAUAAGGUCCUCUCAGCAGAGCCACUGCAGCACCAAAGGCAUUUCUGGAAGGAGGCAAGGACGCGUCAUCUAGAUGUCAAGCCCCAGCGUGCGAUUCUGUCACAGUUCACCCCACCUUCACCCCGAGACGGAAGACGGAAGAGCUUCGCACACAGGCGGGAAGAGGUCAGGACCAGUCCAGCCUCACUGGCUUCAGAACUGGCCUGGGGGCUACCUUGACCCACAGGAAGGGAAGAGGAACGUGCUCUGGGCAGGGCAAGGCAGGACCUGCAGCACCCACAGACCAGCAGUAAAGGACCCCCGGAACUUUCCAAGUCUAGCACAAAACCCAGAAGCCACAAAGGAAAAUACUGGCAGAUUUAAAUGCAUGAAGUCAACAUUCUUUUUGUAGAGCUAAAGAAACCAUAAGCAAAAUUAAAAGCCAAAUGCAUUCUGGGAGGAAA